CCCGCCCGCCGUCCCCGGCGCGACCGGAGCGCCUGACGCUGGGGGGCCGUGUGGGCCCUGACUUCCGGAGGGCUGGGCCCUGGUCCUCCGCCACCGCGUGCGCCCCUUAAAGACCCCUGCCCGCCGCCCAGGACGGAUGGCGACCCCGGCCCUAGCCUGUCCCCAGACCCUGGACCAAGGCCCCGGCCCUGCCCCGAACCCCUCAUCCCACCCCCAGGACCCAGGCCCCGACCCUGGCCACCCAGGACACGCCCUGGCCCUUCCCCGAACUCCCACCCCACAGCUGGGAUCAAGGUCCCGGCCCUGCCCGGAACACCUCACCCCACACCCGGGACCCAGGCCCCGGCCCUGCCCCGAACUCCCACCCCACACCCGGGACCAAGGCCCCGGCCCUGCCCCGAACCCCUCACCCCACCCCCGGGACCAAGGCCCCGGCCCUGCCCAGAACUCCCACCCCACACCCGGGACCAAGGCCCCGGCCCUGCCCAGAACUCCCACCCCACACCCGGGACCAAGGCCCCGGCCCUGCCCCGAAGGCCCCACCGGGGACCCAGGCCCCGGCCCUGCCCCAAACUCCCACCCCACACCCGGGACCAAGGCCCCGGCCCUGCCCCGAACGCCCCACCCGGGACCCAGGCCCCGGCCCUGCCCCAAACUCCCACCCCACACCCGGGACCAAGGCCCCGGCACUGCCCCGAACGCCCCACCAGGGACCCAGGCCCCAGCCCUGUCCCGAACUCCCGCCCCACACCUGAGACGAAGGUCCCGGCCCCGAAGUCCCAACCCCACACCCGGGACCAAGGCCCCGGCACUGCCCCGAACCCCCGCCCCACACCCCUAACCAAGGCCUCGGCUCAGCCCCGGAAUCCCCAACCCCACACCUGGGAUCAAGGCCCCGGCCCUUCCCCAAACCCCCAACCCACACCCGGGACCAAAAGGCCCCGGCCCCACGUUUCCUAGAGGCGCUGGGUUCGGGCCCACGUUGCAACGAGUCAGAUGCUCUUGGUAGCUCAGGGAGGUGUUCACACUCCUGCCGUUUCCGUGAGGAUGGUGACGACUCCGAACUAUAGCAGCAUACUCUACCUACCCCUGAUCAGUUUAUGGAAGAAAAGGAAACCAAACAAAUGGUUUUGCCGUUGUUACUGCUCACCUGGUUUGAUUCAGUGGCGUCGCGGUUGGUCUCUGCUACAGUCCAUUACUCACAGUGCCAGCACAUGUUUCCUUAAAAAGCUUCAUCACCAUCCUCCUGCAAUGCGACCUUCACCGGCUCCCCGUUGCCUGCCCAGGAGGAUAAAGUCCAAGUUCUCCUGUGGAAAGAAGACCCUUCACACGCUAGUCCCAGCCUGUCUUCAGCCCAGCCCCCUGUGUUUCCUUUCCUGCCUUAUCCUAAGACAUCCUUACCUUCCAAUCACACUCACUUUCCGAGCAUUUUUGAAGGUAUUGAGGGAGUUGAUGAGUCUACACUUGAAUAAAAUACAGACUUUACACUCCAGACUGCACAGUUGACAGGUAAGUCCACAGUUCAUAGUGUGGACAGUCCUAUACAAAGAAAUGGAGAGGUGCCCCAGCUCCAGACGCUGCGCUGCUCUGGAAGUCGAGGGCGGCAUUCUUUUGGAGCCUGAGCACUUAGGUCCUAAUGGAUGUGAGUCCCCUGGCCUCAAAUGUGCUUCCUGUACUUGGAUGUCUCCUUCUGGCGGAAUCUCGCUUAUUUUUCAAGUUACAGCCCAAAUGUCAACCACUGAAGUGUUUUAGACAGUUGAUUUUCCUUCUGGGCCCUAUUAUUAGCACUUGUUUGUAGCUCUGUUGAGCUACAUCACAUCAUACAAUUUUCAGCUGACACUACUGUCAUCCCAAAGAAAUGGUCAGGCCUCAAGGGCAGAGGCAGCGAGGGCAGUGAUCUUGGGACAAAGUCUCUACCAAACAAAUACAGCAUGUGUAUUUCUCUAGCAGAGGCCUACAUUUCAAGUGGUGUCUGAGAACAUUCUUUUCUUUUUCUUUUUUCUUUUCUUUUCUUUUUUUUUUUUUUUUUUUUGAGUCUCCCUCUGUCUCCCAGGCUGGAGUGCAGUGGCACAAUCUUGGCUCACUGCAACCUGCGCCUACCGAGUUCAAGUGAUUCUCCUGCCUCAGCCUCCCGAGUAGCUGGGAUUACAGGGAUGCACCAUGAUGCCCAGCUAAUUUUUGUUGUUUUUUUUUUUUGUUUGUUUUUUGUUUUUAGUAGAGUCAGGGUUUCACCAUGUUGGUCAGGCUGGUCUCGAACUCCUGACCUCAAGUAAUCUACCUGCCUCCGCCUCCCAAAAAUGCUGGGAUUACAGGUGAACAUUCUUUUAUUUUAUCCCGAAGCAUUUUCUGUGAAAAAAUAAACACUACUUCUCCAAUGUG